ACUUUGGCUCGAGCACUGCCCUGAGCCGGUCGGGCCCGCGGGCGCCAUGGAGCAGUGGCGGCAGUGCGGCCGCUGGCUCAUCGAUUGCAAGGUCCUGCCGCCCAACCACCGGGUGGUGUGGCCCUCGGCCGUGGUCUUCGACCUGGCGCAGGCGCUGCGCGACGGGGUCCUUCUGUGCCAGCUGCUGCACAACCUCUCCCCCGGCUCCAUCGACCUCAAGGACAUCAACUUCCGGCCGCAGAUGUCCCAGUUUCUGUGUUUGAAGAACAUACGCACCUUCCUGAAAGUCUGCCACGAUAAAUUUGGAUUAAGGAACAGCGAGCUGUUUGACCCCUUUGACCUCUUCGAUGUGCGAGACUUUGGAAAGGUGAGCAGUCACUCUCUCCAGCCUCGGUCGCUCAGCUGUGGUGGCCGAUUUGCCGGCUCAGCGGCAGGUGGGCCAGAUCCAUGGAGCAGCCUGAUUGGCUCCAACACAGAGCCAGUGGAUUUCUGCACCCUCAUGUCCGGGAGGUGCAGGCAGGUCCUGUUACAAACAGGAAGGUGUGAAAGCCAGAUUUGUGUGUCGGGGCUGGGACAACGGGAUGGCCCCUUUCUCUCUCCAGUCAUGGUCAUCUCCGCGGUGUCGAGGCUCUCCCUGCACAGCAUCGCGCAGAACAAAGGGAUCAGGCCUUUUCCCUCAGAGGAGACCACAGAGAAUGACGAUGACGUCUACCGCAGCCUGGAGGAGCUGGCCGACGAGCAUGACCUGGGGGAGGACAUCUACGACUGCGUCCCGUGUGAGGAUGGAGGGGACGACAUCUACGAGGACAUCAUCAAGGUGGAGGUGCAGCAGCCCAUGAAAAUGGGCAUGACUGAAGAUGACAAGAGGAACUGCUGCCUGCUGGAGAUCCAGGAGACCGAGGCCAAGUACUACCGCACCCUGGAGGACAUUGAGAAGAACUACAUGAGCCCCCUGCGGCUGGUGCUGAGCCCGGCGGACAUGGCAGCUGUCUUCAUUAACCUGGAGGACCUGAUCAAGGUGCAUCACAGCUUCCUGAGGGCCAUCGACGUGUCCGUGAUGGUGGGGGGCAGCACGCUGGCCAAGGUCUUCCUCGAUUUCAAGGAAAGGCUUCUGAUCUACGGGGAGUACUGCAGCCACAUGGAGCACGCCCAGAACACACUGAACCAGCUCCUGGCCAGCCGGGAGGACUUCAGGCAGAAAGUCGAGGAGUGCACACUGAAGGUCCAGGAUGGAAAAUUUAAGCUGCAAGACCUGCUGGUGGUCCCCAUGCAGAGGGUGCUCAAAUACCACCUGCUCUUGAAGGAGCUUCUGAGCCAUUCUGCGGAACGGCCUGAGAGGCAGCAGCUCAAAGAAGCACUGGAAGCCAUGCAGGACUUGGCGAUGUACAUCAAUGAAGUUAAACGGGACAAGGAGACCUUGAGGAAAAUCAGCGAAUUUCAGAGUUCUAUAGAAAAUUUGCAAGUGAAACUGGAGGAAUUUGGAAGACCAAAGAUUGACGGGGAACUGAAAGUCCGGUCCAUAGUCAACCACACCAAGCAGGACAGGUACUUGUUCCUGUUUGACAAGGUGGUCAUCGUCUGCAAGCGGAAGGGCUACAGCUACGAGCUCAAGGAGAUCAUCGAGCUGCUGUUCCACAAGAUGACCGACGACCCCAUGAACAACAAGGACGUCAAGAAGUGGUCCUACGGCUUCUACCUAAUUCACCUUCAAGGAAAGCAGGGCUUCCAGUUUUUCUGCAAAACAGAAGAUAUGAAGAGGAAGUGGAUGGAGCAGUUUGAGAUGGCCAUGUCAAACAUCAAGCCAGACAAAGCCAAUGCCAACCACCACAGUUUCCAGAUGUACACGUUUGACAAGACCACCAACUGCAAAGCCUGCAAAAUGUUCCUCAGGGGCACCUUCUACCAGGGAUACAUGUGUACCAAGUGUGGCGUCGGGGCACACAAGGAGUGCCUGGAAGUGAUACCUCCCUGCAAGUUCACUUCUCCUGCAGAUCUGGACGCCUCCGGAGCGGGACCAGGUCCCAAGAUGGUGGCCAUGCAGAAUUACCAUGGCAACCCAGCCCCUCCCGGGAAGCCUGUGCUGACCUUCCAGACGGGCGACGUGCUUGAGCUGCUGAGGGGCGACCCUGAGUCUCCGUGGUGGGAGGGUCGUCUGGUACAAACCAGGAAGUCAGGGUAUUUCCCCAGCUCAUCUGUGAAGCCCUGCCCUGUGGAUGGAAGGCCGCCCAUCAGCCGGCCGCCAUCCCGGGAGAUCGACUACACUGCAUACCCCUGGUUUGCAGGUAACAUGGAGAGGCAGCAGACGGACAACCUGCUCAAGUCCCACGCCAGCGGGACCUACCUGAUCAGGGAGCGGCCUGCCGAGGCUGAGCGCUUUGCAAUAAGCAUCAAGUUCAAUGAUGAGGUGAAGCACAUCAAGGUGGUGGAGAAGGACAACUGGAUCCACAUCACAGAGGCCAAGAAAUUCGACAGCCUCCUGGAGUUGGUGGAGUACUACCAGUGCCACUCACUGAAGGAGAGCUUCAAGCAGCUGGACACCACACUCAAGUACCCCUACAAGUCCCGGGAACGUUCGGCCUCCAGGGCCUCCAGCCGGUCCCCAGUGUUCACGCCCCGCGUCAUCGGCACAGCUGUGGCCAGGUAUAACUUUGCCGCCCGAGAUAUGAGGGAGCUUUCGCUGCGGGAGGGUGACGUGGUGAGGAUCUACAGCCGCAUCGGCGGAGACCAGGGCUGGUGGAAGGGCGAGACCAACGGACGGAUUGGCUGGUUUCCUUCAACGUACGUAGAAGAGGAGGGCAUCCAGUGACGGCAGGAACGUGGACAAGACUCGCAGAUUUUCUUGGGAGAGUCACUCCAGCCCUGAAGUCUGUCUCUAGCUCCUCUGUGACUCAGAGGGGAAAUACCAACCUCCCAGUCUUCCACUGCCCACAGGGAUAGGGAGGGUGUUGAGAAUCCUAAACUCGAACCGUUUCACUGUCAGCCUGCCCUCGGCGACCCAUCACUGGGUAUGCUAUUGUACAUAGAGGAAACCUGGGCUAGCCCCACCCAGAGCGCAGAGGAGGGGGCACCGACAGCGCUGCGAGCCAGGCUCUGGGUAGUGGCUGAGGCCAGAGGCCCAUCGCCUGCCCCUGUCCAACUGAGAUGGCCUUCAGGAGCCUAGGUUUGAACAGCAGAUGCUGUCCCAGGAAGGGCUAGGGACAUCGGAGGGGACCUGCCCCCACACCCUCUGCUCAGCCCCUGGACUCAGCCUUGCCUGUCUUUUCCUGCUGCUCCCAGGGGGAGGUGUCAGACCUCGGGAGGCAGACGGGACCAGAGCCAGGCUGUUCACUGUGGGCCCACUUGCCCCACUGUGCUAGGGCGCGGGAGGAGAGAGCACUGUGGUCGCCCUCUGCAGCCACUCUGGCUCCCAAGACUUCCCUGACUCCCCCACUCCCCUCCUUGCCAGGGGCACACCCGGACCCCACACGGCAGGCCCCUCUCUUGGGAGGGGCCUUUGGAAUGAUGAAAUUCCAACCCUGCUGCCCGGUCAGCGGUACCGUUUCCUGCCCUCUCUCUGAGAGGCCCUUUCUGGAGUCCUGGGAAGGUGUCUGCCUGGCCGCGCUGCCAGAUCAGUACAUCUUUUGUAAAAACCCUGAAAUGGGCAGGGAAGAAAACAGGGAUUUCCCCUCUCUAGAUCCCUGCCAGGUCCCUCUCCAGGAGGCCCCUCUGCUCUCCUGAAGGGUGGUCCCUGAGGGUCUGCCCAGCCUUGGCACGAGAGGUUGGUUCCAGCCCCUGGCAGGGCUUCCUUCCAAGGGCCCCUGCAGCCUACAAACUGGGCCUCGGGCGACUCAAAAUAAGUGCUCUUGGGGGUGGCUCUACCCCAUUACCUCCCCCAGCCACAACUCCUGGCCUUCGACUUCUGGCUGGGUUAGCCAGACCCUGGUUUCUCUACCCUGAUGUUGCAUGAGACCUGGUAACAGUGUCUCCCUCCCAGCUCCUUGCCAAAGCCUCUGUUGAGACCUGGGCUUCUUGUAGCCCCUUCUCCCUCUGGCCAGCUGCACAGCCUGUGGGAGGUGCCCGGCCCAGGCUGGGUGUGGGGGAAGCUGGUCCCUGCUGUGGGUGGCGCUGGGGACCUAGGGGCUCCUUCUGAGGUUGGCCUUGUGGCCUCUGGGCUGUAUGCCUCUGGGGUGUAGGGAAGAGGCGGGAGGAGUCAUGGGGAUGGGGAGCGGCAGGGGGAGAGAGGGGCCCUCGACAAAGGCUUGGGAAAUGAGGGGAGGUGGAGGCAGGGCAGGGGAAGCGAAGAGUCAGCCUUGGAGAGAGCACCCUGGGGCCUCCGUGUCGGGGUACACCCAGCACUUUGCGACCUGCGGCCCAGCAGGCGCGGAGGAUGGCGGGGAGGAAGCCAGCAGCCCCUGUGUUUACUGUCGUCAGAAAGGUCUUGUGUUUUGGUUUUGGGGUUUUUGUUUUGUUUGUGUUUUGUUUGGCUUGUUUGUUUUUUAAGGGGAAAAAAGUUUGUAAUUAUUUCAUCCAAAUCUCCCGUUAUAUAUCUGUGAAUAAUAAGAGAUUUUAUAAUAGCAAGAAAAUGAUGUAUAUUUUAGUUUGUUGACAAAUAAGUCAUCAUGAUCACGAAGGACACUGAGAAAAAAUAAUUUAGAACCCUGGUUUUUGUGAAUUUUUUUGUUUUGUGUUUCUUUGUUUUGAGAUUUGUGUUUGGUUUGGUUUUUGCACUGCACUAAGGCAGGAGGGUUGGAGGGCUGGGUGCAGCCUGGGAGUCCGAUGGUUUUCAGCAGGAGACGGGGUGUCCCCUGCAGGGGGCUAAACUGCAGGGGCCUGAGAUUAGCUGUGAACAUGUGGGAGCCCGAUGCAUGUGGGUCAGGGAUCUGGGGGCCCCCCCAGCUGGCGGGAACCCCAAAUGGACACAAACUGUACAUUUGCCAAUGGGUUUUUUUCAGACCAUGGUUUUUACUUGCAAAUAAACCUGAGUUCUUUUCUGCA